AAAUUCUAGCUAUAUCUAAUGUGUUUUAUUGAAGCAUAUGCUAAAAUGCUGUAUUUGUAAGGAUUCUCAAUGAUACUGGGUAAAUGACUUGUAGUUUCUGAGUGCUGUGGAGUAAAACAAUAGAGAGAUGUCAGAUACUCCAGAGAAGAGGAAGGGUACCUUCAAGAGAGCAUUUCCCUAACAGACUCAGUUAGCUUCAUUUGCCUAACAAACAGACUCAGUUAGCUUUGGCCUUGAAGGUAUUUGCAUGUUAUAGGGCAGGGUUUCCUUUCAUUGAAUACUUUUUAAAAGUGCUUCUUUCUCAUAGCUUAUGUGUACUCCAUUGAAAAAAUGAGGGACAGAAGAGAUAAAGUGCUCUAAAUCUAUUUAGCAGUCCUCAAGGGCAUAACUACAGCCAGAUGUUUAAUGAACUUACUAUGAAUUGUCUUGCAGAGGUACAGAGUGACUUCUUAGGGGUAAACACUUUGCCUGUAACCUGAAUUCAUGCACAAACUUACCUCUAUGACAGGAUCCUGGCUGGAGGGGAGAUUUGCAUUUGGGAGCUGGGCAGGUCCAGGAGGAUGCUCUGUUAAUGGCUCCUCUGGAUUAAGAAGGGGAUCUGUCCUAACGUUGUAGGACAUUCUUCUUAGUUCAGGUAAAGACAGGGUUCUUGUUACAAGACCAUGAAAUAUUAGGCUCAAAGACACUUUGAAGAGUGAGAAAAAUGGAAUUUAUUGGGUGAAAAGGAAAAAAAGGGGAAACAGGGACCCUCAGCGGAGCAAGACUCCUGCUAGUCGGUUUCCCACCUUACAGAUUGAAUCCCAGGUUCCACCCUGGAACAGGAGGGGCCAGGCUCCUCGCCCCUGCAAAGGGCACUAAAUUCUGUGGCCUCACCCCCCAUUCUCCUAGUGUUCUGGGGACCCCUUUACACCUGGCUGUCUCAUUCUCCGCUCUGAAGAAGUCCAUCUGACUGCAGUUAGAAAGGAUAAGGAUGAAGACCCAUCUUAGCCUCCUGCUGACAGGGGGCGCUGUUUUGGGGAAACGGCAGUCAGAGCUCCCUCAAAGACCGAUCUGAGGAUCCCCGGAAGAAGGGGCCAUCAGCUGAGGCUCUGGUUGCGUGAUCAUUUGGAGUUUGAUGGCCUGAAGUUGAGAAGAGACAAACCAGAUGCUGAAGAAUACCAGCCUCCUAUAUGGAAAUCAUACUUAUAUCAGUUACAGCAAGAGGCACCUCGUCCCAAGAGAAUCAUUUGUCCUCGGGAGGUGGAAAACAGACCAAAAUAUUAUGGAAGAGAGUUUCAUGGGAUCAUCUCUCGGGAGCAGGCGGAUGAGCUUCUUGGAGGCGUGGAGGGUGCCUACAUCCUUAGAGAAAGCCAGCGGCAACCAGGAUGCUACACGCUGGCUCUCAGGUUUGGAAACCAGACCUUAAACUACAGGCUCUUCCACGACGGGAAACACUUUGUGGGUGAGAAGAGGUUUGAGUCGAUUCAUGAUCUGGUGACAGAUGGCUUGAUAACACUGUACAUAGAAACAAAAGCUGCCGAGUACAUUUCAAAAAUGACAACUAACCCCAUCUAUGAACACAUUGGAUAUGCCACCCUACUCAGAGAAAAAGUAUCCAGAAGGCUGAGCAGGUCUAAAAAUGAACCAAGAAAAACAAACGUCACACAUGAAGAACACACAGCGGUGGAAAAGAUCUCCUCCCUGGUUCGAAGGGCUGCCCUCACACACAACGACAACCACUUCAAUUAUGAGAAGACACACAACUUUAAGGUCCACACGUUCCGAGGCCCACACUGGUGUGAAUAUUGUGCCAAUUUCAUGUGGGGGCUCAUCGCCCAAGGGGUCCGGUGCUCAGACUGUGGAUUGAACGUACACAAACAGUGUUCCAAGCACGUUCCCAAUGACUGCCAACCUGAUCUCAAGAGGAUCAAGAAAGUGUACUGUUGUGACCUCACAACACUUGUGAAGGCUCACAACACUCAGAGACCCAUGGUGGUAGACAUAUGCAUUCGGGAAAUUGAAGCAAGAGGAUUAAAAUCGGAAGGCCUUUACAGAGUCUCUGGGUUCACUGAACACAUUGAAGAUGUCAAAAUGGCAUUUGACAGAGAUGGUGAAAAGGCCGAUAUAUCUGCCAAUGUCUAUCCAGACAUAAACAUCAUCACUGGAGCCCUUAAACUGUAUUUCAGAGACUUACCCAUCCCUGUCAUCACAUAUGAUACCUAUUCCAAAUUUAUAGAUGCAGCAAAAAUCUCCAAUGCAGAUGAGAGGCUGGAAGCCGUCCAUGAAGUGCUGAUGCUGCUGCCUCCUGCCCACUAUGAAACCCUCCGGUACCUAAUGAUCCACCUCAAAAAGGUUACUAUGAAUGAAAAAGACAAUUUCAUGAAUGCAGAAAAUCUGGGGAUCGUGUUUGGGCCCACUCUGAUGAGGCCCCCUGAGGACAGCACCCUGACCACCCUGCAUGAUAUGCGGUACCAAAAGCUGAUUGUGCAGAUUUUAAUAGAAAACGAAGACGUUUUAUUCUAAUCCAUCAGGGAAAUGAGCUGAAUGGCCCCAGCACCAUCCAAGUUGACACAGCUAAAGGAAUAAAAACAUUUCUUACCACUUGAUUUGUUUUCCAAGCAAGUGCUAGAAUUUCCUGGACUGCAGAGGAUCGCUGAGUGGGGUACUGUGUCUCAUAGACAUGCGCCACCUCCACGUGAGAACAAGGGUGAAGGUGAGGGAAGCCCCUCACCUUGGGUCUUUUGCUGUGCCUCCUAUGUAUGUCUGGUUUGCUGGAAGAGUGAUUAAUACAUCUUUAAUUUAUUAAAAAACAAUGUAGACCUUUAAACUUCAGUCUUAUUGGUAAUAAAAGGGAACUUAAUUCAUACAGGUACUUGAUACAGUUAUACAUUUUCCACUUACAAAAAGAAGACAAUUCUGUUAAAUGAAACGUGUAUCGUAAAAUGUAUUUUUAUUUUACCCACGAGAAUGUUGUUAUUUUUAGCAAAUAGAACUCAAUGCAGUGCAUUGGUUAUUACCCUGUGUACCUUGUCCCUCAUUUUGCUGUGACACCCUGAAAAAGCUGACCACAAAUGCAGUAUUAUCUUGACAUACCUCUGUCCUCCUCAGUGCUUUUUAAUGAAAUUUCACCUGCCCCUUGUGUUCCUGCUUUGGAUAGUUUUUGCUCUUAAGCAUUGGCAUUCUUCUAUUGUAUGGUAUGUAUUUAUAGCAAUUGUAGGAUGGUCUGAAAUGUCCACACACUUUCUAUGCAUACAAAUUUUGUGAAUUCCCAAAGUAUGCUUUGGAAUUGGUCAUAGUCUUUUCGUAUCAUGAGUGUGUAUCCCAGAAGAUACAGAAUGCGGUCAUUUUACCUGAAAUUAUUUGAGAACACUGGAUGUAUCUGGUCUGUGUAAAAAGUUAGCACUUACCCUCUUUUCUUCCUGGCCAAGCCCUCUGAAUUCAUCUGUUAAUAUCAAAUUGUAUUUUUGCCACAUUUCUGUAUUGGUGAAAAGCGAAUCUGCAGAAUAACUGUCAACGUUUUUCAUUCUUGUUUUACAAACCUAUUUUUUAAAGUGAGAAUAAGGUUGGUUUUUACCAAAUAUUUGUUCCUCCUUGACAAAAGUAGCUCUGUGUGGAUAAUAUGAUUUUAUUACUACAGUUCCAGUCACUUGGUUAUAUUUAUCUUAGCAUGAGCCUUUCACACCAAGAUUUCUAUAUUUUGUAACAUAGGUGAAAUAUUUAAAACAUCAAAAACUGUAAAUCUAGAUUUUUAAAAAAUCCAACUGCAAUGUCUUUUCCUUUGAUUGAGAUGAUUUGUGUAAACUCACCAGUCUUGCUUUGGAGUGAGCAGAAGAGAAUGACUAUUUUACGUGGAGCAUCAUUGUGUGACUGUUGACCUGGACAGUCCCAAGGGCUAUGCAGAUGGACUCCAUUGGCACAGGGAGGUUUGACCUCUUCCCUGCUAUUAUCCCUCCUCCCAACUGUACAGAUUUGUUUGUUGUAGUUUAUGUACUUCUUGAUACUGUCAAAAAAUUAUCUGGAAAUGGUUUUAUUUUGUGAAGUGAACAAUACUUUGUAAUUUAUGAUAGUGUAAAUGGAAGGCAAAGCAUCACAUGUAUUAAAUUCUUCUGUCUAUUA